AGUCUCCGCCCGCCGAUCCGGCCUCUUCGGCCGUUGCGCACUCCACCCCCUCCCUCCGCGCCCGCGCGCGCCUUCCCCGCCCCGUCCGCCUCACUCCUUUUGGGGCGGUUGGGCCGCGCGCCUGUGGGGGCGGGGCCCGGAGCAGGCCACCGAGCCAAUGGGGCGCGGCGGCGGCGGCGGCGGUGGUGGCGGCGGCGGCGGAGGCGGCGGUGGCGGCGGUGGCGGCUGGGUCGGGCCCCGACGGGCGGCGGCGGCUGAGGUGGAGGCGGAGGGAGGCGGCGGCGGCGGCGGCGGGAAGAUGGCGGCUCCCGUCCUGCUAAGAGUGUCGGUGCCGCGGUGGGAGCGGGUGGCCCGGUAUGCAGUGUGCGCUGCCGGAAUCCUGCUCUCCAUCUACGCCUACCACGUGGAGCGGGAGAAGGAGCGGGACCCCGAGCACCGGGCCCUCUGCGACCUGGGGCCCUGGGUGAAGUGCUCCGCCGCCCUUGCCUCCAGGAAAAGAAAGUUUGAGCCCAGAGGAAAGUUAACAGACAAAGAUUCUGAAGAAAAUCAUCUUCCAGGAUCCAGAGUCAGCACGUGGUUUUGGAUUGCUCAAACUCACUUUAUUCUCAUUUCGCAAGCCCUGUGUCUUAAUCCAAACACGAUGGGGUCGAGGAUUUGGUCUUUUGGGUUCCAUUUUUGGAAAGGAUGGUGUAUUAAACCAGCCAAACAGUGUCUUUGGACUUAUAUUUUAUAUACUACAGUUAUUACUUGGCAUGACAGCAAGCGCUGUGGCGGCUUUGAUCCUCAUGACGUCCUCCAUCAUGUCGGUCGUGGGGUCCCUGUACCUGGCCUACAUUCUGUACUUUGUGCUGAAGGAGUUCUGCAUCAUCUGCAUCGUCACGUACGUGCUGAACUUCCUUCUUCUCAUUAUCAACUACAAACGACUAGUUUACUUGAACGAGGCCUGGAAGCGGCAGCUGCAACCCAAGCAGGACUGACGCCCGACAGACUCCACCCUAACAGUCUCAAGCCCCUUUCCAUUCAGUUUAUUUUGCAGCAGGUUUUUAUUAUUAUUAUUAUUAUUAUUAUUCACAACAGACACUUUCCCUAAGAAUCUCAAACUGAUUUUUAAAAAUCCGGUAAAUUAGAAGGGGCCCUCGCUAUUUUCUGUGUCAGUCUUCAUUUUAAAUAUGGAUACAAAAAGGAUACGCCGAGCCAAUCAAAGACAAGCUUUAACUUUACUUUGAAGUGUUUCUGAAAUGAUAAAAUGUAGCCCUAGCCCCCUGCCCUCAAUUGUAAAGUGAGCAACCAUUGCUAGUAAUUCUUUAAUGUGUAUAAAUUCAAUUUCAGGUAUAACAAAUGUGAUCAUGACAUGAAAAUAUUCUAGAAUAGAUACUGUAUUAAAUAUUGCCAUGUUUACAAUAUGUAAUAUGUUUUUAGCCGAUGGAUUUAAACAUGUAGAUUCAACUAGAAUCCAUUUGUGAUAUUUGUAAAUAAAGGUAGAAAUAUUAGAUCCAUUUCUGCAGAACUUACUGUACAGUUUAGUUGGAGUGUAGCACUGAAGAACUGUCAGCUCAGCGUUGACUGAGGAGAUAGUGAAAAUAGCCUAUACACAGCAUCUUGUGAAAAGUACUGGCAGCCGUGGUUGCAGCAAAUAAUAGGGCAAAAAAAAUAAUAAUAGGGUGGUCGGUUCCCUUUCAUCUCCCUCUUCUGAAAGGAAAAAAUUGAAUUGGAACGUUCAAGUCCAGUUUGUGUUCAGUCAUAAAACUGGGCCAGUUGUUAACCUUACAGAAUGAGUCAUGUGGCCAGACCUUCAAGUCCAAGGCCUUCAGACACUAAGGAUGGGAAAAUGGGUAUUUUUCUUUGGAGAAAAGCUGGAAAUAUAAACAUGGCAUUUUUAGGUAAAGUUUCUUCCACUAGUUGAAUUUUCAUGCAGAUAUUUUUCCUUAACGUUGGUGCCAGUCAAGCAAAGAGUAUUAUGAUGGAAAAGACCAGUCCAAGCCCCAUCGCUCCGGAGUGGGAGCCAGUGUUCUUGCUAAUUGUUUCUUUCUGCACUAACCACUCAGAUGUCUAAUUUAAUUGUUUUGCAGUCAAAUACUGGAUUUGUAACCUUCAGGGCUGACAUGCUGCCCAGUUUGCUUCAUCGGGAGAAUAGCAACAGGUAGACACAUCUCAAGGCUAAAUCUGCUCAUGUCGCCACUGCUCUCAUAAUGACACACAUGCAGUAAGAAGACUUUUGUAAGGGGAUUUGAGUACACCCAAAUGAAAUUGUGACAGGAUGUUUGUAUGGUUAACAUCUGAUAUCAGAAUGUUAAAAGUGCCUUCUGUCUUAAAUCUCAAACCAAAUAUUUUGUGUGUUGACCUUGGGCAGAAGAAGUGUCCUUCCCUCCUUUCUUCACCGUCAGGUAGAAAACCUGCACUCUGCAGAAGGGUCCUGUGUGAUCACUUAAUCCUCUGGUUGAGAAGCAGCAGUAAUGUUUUUGCUUCCAACCUGAUUAAUCAUUUUAUGUUGAAAAUAGUCAAUGAGACCAGUAUCUCUUGAGUGCUUUAUUUGCCUUCUCUUUGAAGGGAGGGGACGGGCUCUGCUCUGUAAACUCAAAUGUGUAGAGUCAGCAACAAUUCCGUAGCUUCCAACUGACUCAGAAUUGAUGCAACGUAGGUCUUCUGGCCCGAGGCAGGUAUCAAGUCCAAAUCAUAAUGAACUUUUCACCAGUUUCAACCAGUUUCUUAAAAGAGAGCUUAAGUCAAGAUUUCAUCAAGACUUGUGUUUUCCCAUGAAUGUGAAUCUUUCAAUGGCUGUUGGAGUAUGUAUGUACUGUUCUUGCAUUCUGAAGUAGUUAAAGAACUCUAGAAAGUACUGAUUGGCCAUCUGGUGUCUAUGGAGAAAGAAGUCCUCACGUUUGAGGGCUGUACAGUGAGGCCAUCUUGUAGCAGCGCAUCCAGCUCUACCAAGGCAGUCCUCUGGUUCUUUUUUCUAAGCUACAGUGGAAAUGGCCUAAUGGUUAAAACUGUGGUAUACAUGACAUCGGUUGUGCUAAACAAGUUCCUCGUGUCCCAAUAUCCAAUGGUUUUUCAUCCUAUUUUGUAUCAAUCAACAGAGUAUAGUUAAAGCUUGUCUUGAUGUUGCAUUCUUGCAAAUGUCUUCAACUCUUACCUGAGAAAACAUGGCAAAAUGGUCAGCCAGACCCUUCCAGUUUUUCCUUUGCUUUUCUAAGCCUCGGGGAAACCACUGUUUCAGUUGUAUAAAAACUUUUGCCACAUUCCUAUGGCCCAGUCGAAUUAAUACCCUUUUUCUCACUGAGAGAGGAACACGUACUGCCUGUCAUAACAGCAUUGUAAUGCCAGUGUCUCAGUAACAGAAUCCUGGUGGGUGUUAAUUGGGUGUUUUUUGCCCUGGAGAAUUCAGAUUCCUUUCUAUACCUCCGAUUCUGCCCAGAAGAGGGGGGGAAUCACCAGUGUUACAAAAUUAGAAGAUUGUUUUGCCUGUUUUAGACUGAAUAUUUGAACACUGCAGCAUUACUAGCCACCAGUGUUAAAGGACAGAUGAGGGGAAACAUUUGUUUUUAGCAGUAAUUCCAUGCCUCAUCUUUUUUAAGUGAUUUGUUCCAAAUGAAGCCAUUUAUUGACUUGAUGUUCACAAAUAUCAUUUGAAGAAAUAACAGGAAUUGGGGUUAGAUGAUAAAUUCUAGGGAAUCUAGGUGAUUUGGAGGAUUUCAUUUGUUUUGCAUUACAGCUAGUUGCUCUCACUAAAGGUAAAUUUCCGGUGAAAUAACUCAGGUUUAACUAGCUGUGUGCCCAGAAUCACUGUUCCUUCAUACAUGUGUCCUCUCCUUAAAUUCAUUACUUUCAAAUGAUGUUCAAAGCAUUGACUAUUUUCAUUCAAAGAAACUACAUUCGGCCGGGCACGGUGGCUCACGCCUAUAAUCCCAGCACUUUGGGAGGCCGAGGCGGGUGGAUUACCUAAGGUCAGGAGUUCAAGACCAGCCUGGCCAGCAUAGUGAAACCCCAUCUCUACUAAAAAUACAAAAAUUAGCCAGGCGCAGUGGCACACCCCUGUAAUCCCAGCUACUCGGGAGGCUGAGGGAGGAGAAUUGCUUGAGCCCGGGAGACAGAGGUUGCAGUGAGUCAAGAUCAUGCCACUGCACUCCAGCCUGGCCAACAGAGCGAGACUGUCCCCCCCCCAAAAAAAAAAGAGAGAGACUGCAUUCAAAGAGGACCAAGACUACAGUGAAAUUAAAACUGUUUGCUGGCUGGGCAUGGUGGCUCACACCUGUAAUCCCAGCACUUUGGGAGGCCGAGGCGGUUGGAUCACCUGAGGUCAGAAGUUCGAGAUCAGCCUGACCGACAUAGUGGAACCCUGUCUUUACUAAAAAUACAAAAAUUAGCUGGGCAUGGUGGCGGCACCUGUAAUGCCAGCUCCUCCAGAGGCUGAGGCAGGAGAAUUGCUUGAACCCAGUAGGUGGAGGUUGCAGUGAGCCACAGUUGCGCCAUUGCACUCCAGCCUGGGCAAUGAGUGAAACUCUGUCUCAAAUAAAAAAAUAAAAAUAAAAACUAUUUGUUGACUUUUGUUUUUCAUUUAGUUUUGGAAAAGACUAUUUGCAAAAGUACAGAGUUAUCUUCAGCAAUUACUUCACAACUUAGAUUGGUACCAAGAGUGACAGGAGAUCUUGUCUUGGAAGAUCAUUAUUAGAUGCCAACAAGGAGACCCACUGUGAUUUCUGGUAACCUAUUUGGGGAAAAAGACCUAAUGACCUAAUAUGCAAUUUCUGUCCUCGUGUCUUUUUCUCUAACACACAGUCAUGGGUGAAACAUUUCAGACACCUCAGGCAGCACUUAUGGUUUCUAAUUGUGAGAACUACCCUUCCAUCAAACAAAAAGGGCAAGGGUGGGAGCCCCGGCUACUUGGUUAAACAUUUUUUACUACAAAUUCGCCCAGAAAAGGUGAAAUAUUUUGUUAUAAAACUGUAUUAAGCAUGGCCUAAGUAUUUAUUAGGUAUAUGAUCUGUGUAGUAUGUUCCAUCAGAAAUAUUUCUUACUAGUGCUUUAAGCUCCAGAGUAAACAGUCAUUUAAAAUGGAGUUCACUGGGCAGGUUUCCCCUUUAAUCUAGAUAGAAAUACUCUUUAUCAGAGAUUUAAGGCACUGUUUUGCUAACUGGUAAAUAAAACCAAAUGUAAAUAUGUAAGAAUGUUUAUUUGUUGCACAUAACUUUUUUGGUAUAAAAUAAAUGUAGAAGUUACCUGUGGAAGUUGUGCUCCCAUUAUUCUUAAACUGCAGGGUUGCAUUCCAAAAGAACUGAAACGAAGUCUUUUUAGACUCAGUAGGAGCCUUAUAUUCUUGAAGUCAAUACUGUAACCUCAUUUCUAAGGUAUACAGGGUUGAUUCUUUUUCUCUUAAAUCAUAUGUAACUUGCAGAAGAUUCAGAGUCCUCAGACCUCUAGUUCUUGGAAUUCCUGUAGGUUUACGGUGUAUGUGAUUGUCAAGAAUUAAUGACAAAAAUGUGUCACUGCCUACAGUUCUGUGAACACUCAGAAUGUAUUAAUGAGCUGUUUUUCCAUAGUUUUACUUUAGCUUACCUUGAAUACUCCCUGUAUAAUCCUCUAAAAAGGUAGCAUCGGCAAGAAAGAUGAAUCCGUUGGAAAUACAGCUGAGCCAUACUUCACGGAAUAGAACAAGUGUGUUCUGUGCUGGAGCUCAAGACCUGUGGAAAGGGACUGCCCCCACUGGGUGCAAUGGCUCAUGCCUGUAAUCCCAGCACUUUGGGAGGUAGAGGCGGGUGGAUCACUUGAGGUCAGGAGUUCAAGACCAGCCUGGCCAACAUGGUGAAACCUGCCUCUACUGAAAAAUACAGAAAAAUUAGCCAGGAUUGUGGUGUGCGCCUGUAAUCCCAGCUAUUCAGGAAGCUGAGGCAGGAGAAUUGCUUGAACCAGGGAGGCGGAGGUUGCAGUGAGACGAGAUCACGCCACUGCACUGCAGCCUAGGCGACAGAGGAAGACUCCAGCUCAAGAAAAAAAACAAUGGACUGCCCCUAAUUUGUAAACCAUUUAAAUGUGUCUAUUACAUUUAACUUUUCUUAAUGUUUGUCAACUAAAAGUUUUAUUCAUUAUACUUUGACAUACUGGAACACAAAACUUGAUUCCUUUGAAAAACUAAAGAGAAGUUGAUAAAAAAAAUACAGAAGCUCUAGAUUCCUAAUUGGAACUGACUACACUCAUUUUUAAAAAAUGGACGAUGCCUAAUAAAACCACAUGAAAUUAA